CUUUUGGCAACCCACACCCUUCCACACACGCUCACCCCAAAAUUAAACACCAAGAUCCUCUAACUUGUUUGGAUUGACUGAUGAAGACAUAAAGCUCUAUGUUUUUUGAGGUGGAGUGAGUGGUUUUUCUUCAUUUUUAAAUGGCCAAAUGACAGCUUGACCCAGUUUGCUUUCCAAUCAAAGGGCAUUUAUUUUGAAUGUCUCUUUGUGGCGCAAGAGCCAACGCAAAAAUGAUGGCGGCUUACAAUGGCGGUACAUCUGCAGCAGCAGCAGGUCACCACCACCACCAUCACCACCACCUUCCACACCUCCCUCCUCCUCACCUGCACCACCACCACCACCCUCAACACCAUCUUCAUCCGGGGUCGGCUGCCGCUGUACACCCUGUACAGCAGCACACCUCUUCGGCAGCUGCGGCAGCCGCAGCAGCGGCUGCAGCUGCAGCCAUGUUAAACCCUGGGCAACAACAGCCAUAUUUCCCAUCACCGGCACCGGGGCAGGCUCCUGGACCAGCUGCAGCAGCCCCAGCUCAGGUACAGGCUGCCGCAGCUGCUACAGUUAAGGCGCACCAUCAUCAGCACUCGCAUCAUCCACAGCAGCAGCUGGAUAUUGAGCCGGAUAGACCUAUUGGAUAUGGAGCCUUUGGUGUUGUCUGGUCAGUAACAGAUCCAAGAGAUGGAAAGAGAGUAGCGCUCAAAAAGAUGCCCAACGUCUUCCAGAAUCUGGUCUCUUGCAAAAGGGUCUUCCGGGAAUUGAAGAUGUUGUGUUUUUUUAAGCAUGAUAAUGUACUCUCUGCCCUUGACAUACUCCAACCUCCACACAUUGACUAUUUUGAAGAAAUAUAUGUUGUCACAGAAUUGAUGCAGAGUGACCUACAUAAAAUUAUCGUCUCUCCUCAACCACUCAGCUCAGAUCAUGUCAAAGUUUUUCUUUAUCAGAUUUUGCGAGGUUUGAAAUAUCUCCAUUCAGCUGGCAUUUUACAUCGAGACAUUAAGCCAGGGAAUCUCCUUGUGAACAGCAACUGUGUUCUAAAGAUUUGUGAUUUUGGAUUGGCCAGAGUGGAAGAAUUAGAUGAAUCCCGUCAUAUGACUCAGGAAGUUGUUACUCAGUAUUAUCGGGCUCCAGAAAUCCUGAUGGGCAGCCGUCAUUACAGCAAUGCUAUUGACAUCUGGUCUGUGGGAUGUAUCUUUGCAGAACUACUAGGACGAAGAAUAUUGUUUCAGGCACAGAGUCCCAUUCAGCAGUUGGAUUUGAUCACGGAUCUGUUGGGCACACCAUCACUGGAAGCAAUGAGGACAGCUUGUGAAGGCGCUAAGGCACAUAUACUCAGGGGUCCUCAUAAACAGCCAUCUCUUCCUGUACUCUAUACCCUGUCUAGCCAGGCUACACAUGAAGCUGUUCAUCUCCUUUGCAGGAUGUUGGUCUUUGAUCCAUCCAAAAGAAUAUCCGCUAAGGAUGCCUUAGCCCACCCCUACCUAGAUGAAGGGCGACUACGAUAUCACACAUGUAUGUGUAAAUGUUGCUUUUCCACCUCCACUGGAAGAGUUUAUACCAGUGACUUUGAGCCUGUCACCAAUCCCAAAUUUGAUGACACUUUCGAGAAGAACCUCAGUUCUGUCCGACAGGUUAAAGAAAUUAUUCAUCAGUUCAUUUUGGAACAGCAGAAAGGAAACAGAGUGCCUCUCUGCAUCAACCCUCAGUCUGCUGCUUUUAAGAGCUUUAUUAGUUCCACUGUUGCUCAGCCAUCUGAGAUGCCCCCAUCUCCUCUGGUGUGGGAGUGAUGGUGGAAGAUAAUGUACUACUGAAGAUGUAAUGUAGCUUUCCACUGGAGUCUGGGAUUUGCAAUUCUGGAGGUUAAUCAUGCUUGUACUGUAAUUUUACUAAUGAAGUUUUAAAUUAACAACCACUACUUGUAUGAUAUGAAUAAUAUUUAGAAAUGUUACUAGACUUUUAAUCUUGUAAAGUGGUUGUGCUUUUAGAAGAAAAAUAUUUUACCCAGAGUUGCACAUGUUUUAUGAAUUUAGUGCAGCUGUUAUGGCUCACCUCAGAACAAAAGAGAAUUGAACCAAAUUUGGGAGUUUGGGGUUUUAUGUUUUGUUUUUCUUUUCUAAAAUGAAGUGAGAUUGUUCACACACACACACACACACACACACACACACAAACACAAAGGACAGUCAUACAUUUUGAUAUUUGAGCCAUUCCUAAAGAUUUGGGGUUUUCUAAAACUAAAGAAUCUAGGAACCUUGCCUGCGACCAAUCAUGGAGCCACGUGAGCUGAUCGUGGCUGCACCUGGGGGGAGGGUAGGGAGGAGGGGCAUGCCACCUAAUGAUCAAGCCCUAUAAUUAGCUUCUCAUUAGAGCCGUGAUGGUGAUGUGUGCUGUCUAAAAUCCAAUGUUGUGGGUAGAGAGAAUGAGUUUGUGACUAGGAGAGACUAAACUUUUGUUUUCCUUACCCAGUAUAAAUAUAUAUAUAUAUAUUUAAUCUAUUUUUAUUAGAAGUUUUUCUGCUCUUUCUUACAUAAAAGAACCCCAAGCAUGCAUCUUUCAUGUGUGUAAAUAAUUCAUUUCUGGGCUAAUUUCAAAAGAAUCCCAAUAUUGCUGUAUAGAAAGAGAACUAGCUUGCACAUUUUAGGUCUGUGAAAUUUUGUGAGACUUUUCCUGCACUGGACAGUAAAAAAAUAAUAAAAGACAAAAACAAAUUUAAAAAAAAAUUUAAGCCACAAAAAAAGGCACAUAGGGAAUUAUGUCAAAUGUGUUUGUGUCCUUAGGCAAAGCUGUGGGAGUCUUGAAAUGUCACAGUAGUAAAUAACUUAUUACUUUUUGACAAGUUCUUUUUUUCUGUUGGAACACUGAAUUCUUCUGUGCAUAUGUACAUAUGAAUACAAAUCGAAGGCCUCUACCUCCUGGAGUUAUACAACUUGGCUUGUUUACCUCCACAUGCUGAUGAUGACUAUUUUUUUUUUUUGAGUUCAGUGUGGAGACUUGAAACUUGAAUGUCCCUUCCAACUUUUAUAUUAAAAAUAAAAAGACAAGAAAAUUGAAGAUCAUUUUUCACCUGUACAAGGAAUACUAAUGGAUCGUCUUAAAAUUGGUCUAGGAAAAAACCUUGGUGUGUGUUAUGGACAAUUAACUGUUAAAGUUAUUGUAAGUUAUCUGUAUUUAGCAGAGUAUUUUCAACUUGAGUGAUCUGAGCUGAAUUUGAAGACUAUUAAUAAGUUAUGUUUGGAAGUUUUAACUUCAAUGAAGUAAUUAUUUGCUGUGAAAGAAACAAACAUUGAAUUACUAAACAAAGAUGGUGCAAUAUCUUUGUUUUUUUUUUAUGAGGCUCCUGAGAAUCAACCCAACUGAAGCAUUUCAAUUCACUUGAAUGAGAAACGUGUUUAGUAUCAAAAGAGCCCAAGAAGACACUGGUGUGAAAGGUACAAUCUCAGAGGUUGGUCAAUUACCGUGGCACACUUUCUGGUCACUUUGUACAAUGUAGAUUUGAAGUACAGUGGUGAAAACAUUAAAUGUGACAUUUGAAAAA